AAAUCGGUACAAGAUGGCGGAGGGGGACGAGGCAGCGCGAGGGCAGCAACCGCACCAGGGGCUGUGGCGCCGGCGACGGACCAGCGACCCAAGCGCCGCGGUUAACCACGUCUCGUCCACGACCUCCCUAGGUGAGAAUUAUGAAGAUGAUGACCUAGUAAAUUCUGAUGAGGUUAUGAAGAAACCAUGUCCAGUACAGAUUGUUCUUGCUCAUGAAGAUGACCAUAACUUUGAACUUGAUGAAGAAGCUUUGGAGCAGAUAUUGCUACAGGAGCACAUACGAGAUCUUAACAUAGUAGUGGUAUCUGUGGCAGGAGCUUUUCGUAAAGGGAAGUCAUUUCUACUGGACUUCAUGCUUAGAUACAUGUAUAACAAGGAUUCUCAAAGUUGGAUUGGUGGAAACAAUGAACCAUUGACAGGCUUUACAUGGCGAGGUGGCUGUGAAAGAGAAACAACAGGCAUACAAGUUUGGAAUGAAGUAUUUGUGAUUGACAGACCUAAUGGAACUAAAGUUGCUGUGCUGCUUAUGGAUACCCAGGGUGCCUUUGAUAGCCAGUCAACUAUCAAAGACUGUGCAACGGUGUUUGCUCUGAGCACUAUGACUAGCUCUGUCCAGGUGAGACACAAGAUUAAGUGGUGCGAUCAGUUCACGUAAUCAUUUGGCCCCUUUUUUUUUUCUUUUUUGAGACAGAGUUUCACUCUUGUUGCCCAGGCUGGAGUACAGUGGCGUGAUCUCGGCUCACUGCAACCUCUGCCUCCUGGGUUCAUUCUCCUAACCCGAGUAGCUGAGAUUACAGGCCCCCGCCACCAUGCCCAGCUAAUUUUUUUGUAUUUUUAGUAGAGACGGGUUUCACCACGUUGGGCAGGCUGGUCUCGAACUCCUGACCUCAGGUGACCCGCCCACCUCGGCCUCCCCAAGUGCUGGGAUUACAGGCGUGAGCCACUGAGCCUGGCAUUUGCCCCUCUUGAAAAUGCCUUUUUAAUUUUUUUUGAGAUGGAUUCUCACUAUGUUGCCCAGGUUGGAGUGCAGUGGCUAUUCAUGGGUGUGAUCAUGCACACUCUAGCUUUUGGGCUGAAGUGAUCCUCCUGCCUCAGCCUCCUGAGUAGCUGGGACUGUCAGCAUAUGCCACCUUGUGCUGGCAAAAUGCCUUUUGAUUGAAGGGAAAAAAAAGGAAGCUAUUUACAUUUCUUGAGAGCUAUUUACAUUUCUUAUUGGUUAUUUACAUUUCCAUGCAUGGUUUUCUGGCUUAUGAUGUGAAAUUUUGUACUUUGGAUAGUUACAAAGGAUGCAAUAAACCAACAACCAGUCUCUUUAGUUUUUCAUUAUGGAAUACAUACUUUUUUUUUUAAAGGAAAAGAUAUCACAUGUUAUCUGUAAUUGAAAUCAGAUAGAUGGCUACCAGACACAGUAAUAUGGAGAGUAUAUUUUUGUUUUUUUGGCUAAAACAAACAAAAAACCCAGGUAAUUAAGCUUAGAAGUCUAGUUUUUUAUUCUGUAUCUAUGACAAGUGGUACUCAGUUAUUUGAACUAAAGGAGAUAAAAGCAGAGUAAUUACUUAAUGUUUAAUUUAGGAAACCCAGACAAGGCUUAUGUAAUAAUAAACUGAGGAUUUUUAGCACCUUCAUUUAGGAAGGGAUAAAAUCCCUUCUCUUUUUCACUUAUAUUCAAAUUGUGUUUGGUGUUCUAUCCGGUUCUAGUUUCUUCAGGCUAGGCCAUUUCUUUUCUGUAUAAUUUAGAUGGAUUGGACUGAAUUAAACUACCACAUGUCAUUUGGUGUUUCUUUACUUUUUCUUUUCUGAGAUCAUCUGUGGCUGAUACAUCUCUGAAAAAUGAAUUAUUGAAGUAUGGCGGUUAGGCCCAGCUGGUGAUGGUGUAUCAAGAAGUAUAUUUGCAAAUAUUUUUUUAAAAUGGGUAUAUAAUCUGUCUCAGAAUAUUCAAGAAGAUGAUCUUCAACAUUUGCAAUUAUUUACAGAGUAUGGAAGACUUGCGAUGGAAGAAAUCUACCAGAAACCAUUUCAGACAUUAAUGUUUUUGAUUCGAGAUUGGAGCUAUCCUUAUGAACAUUCAUAUGGUUUGGAAGGUGGAAAGCAAUUUCUUGAAAAGAGAUUACAGGUAAAACAAAAUCAACAUGAAGAGCUUCAGAAUGUAAGGAAGCACAUACACAAUUGUUUCUCAAAUCUUGGUUGCUUCCUUUUGCCACAUCCUGGUCUUAAAGUUGCAACUAAUCCUAGUUUUGAUGGGAGAUUGAAAGAUAUUGAUGAAGACUUUAAACGAGAGCUUCGAAAUCUGGUUCCAUUGCUGCUUGCCCCUGAAAAUUUGGUAGAAAAAGAGAUAAGUGGAUCUAAAGUCACUUGUAGAGAUCUUGUAGAAUAUUUUAAGGCUUACAUCAAAAUCUAUCAAGGAGAAGAACUUCCACAUCCAAAGUCCAUGCUUCAGGCAACAGCUGAAGCUAAUAAUCUUGCUGCAGUAGCAGGAGCAAGAGAUACCUAUUGUAAAAGUAUGGAACAGGUAUGUGGAGGGGACAAGCCUUACAUUGCACCUUCAGAUCUGGAGCGAAAACACUUGGAUCUCAAGGAAGUGGCGAUAAAACAAUUUCGUUCAGUAAAAAAGAUGGGUGGAGAUGAGUUCUGCCGUCGUUAUCAGGACCAGCUUGAAGCUGAAAUUGAAGAAACCUAUGCAAAUUUUAUAAAGCACAAUGAUGGCAAAAAUAUCUUCUAUGCUGCUCGUACCCCAGCCACACUGUUUGCGGUCAUGUUUGCUAUGUAUAUAAUCUCAGGACUGACUGGCUUCAUUGGCCUAAACUCUAUAGCUGUCUUGUGUAACCUUGUCAUGGGGUUAGCACUGAUAUUUCUUUGUACUUGGGCAUAUGUUAAAUACUCUGGGGAGUUCAGAGAAAUUGGAACAGUGAUUGAUCAGAUUGCUGAAACACUAUGGGAACAGGUAUUGAAGCCCCUGGGUGAUAAUUUGAUGGAGGAAAACAUAAGGCAGUCUGUAACAAACUCUAUCAAAGCAGGCCUGACUGACCAGGUGUCUCAUCAUGCCAGAUUAAAGACAGACUGACAGUUCAUCUCCUCACGGACUCCACUCUCUUUUUUUUUCAUGCUUGCUGUACAAUGAGAACUCAAAUAAAAAUAAACCAAAGUUUACAAUCAACUGUAGAAGUAGUUUAGUGUAACUGGCUUCACAGAUGGCUGCCACAGAGUGUGAAGAUUGUUUGUUAGUUUUAAGCAUUCUUUUAAUGGCUCCUAAGACAUGCAGAUGGACUGAGGAGCAUUGGUUAAUCAUGCACCUUUGUGCCAUGUUUAACUCUUUUAUUUCUUUUUACUUAAUCUAAUGUUAGUGAAUUUGUCUUAUGUAAAAGGAUAUUUCAGGGAAAUAUUUUCAGAAAUCUAUUUAGAGUCUCUUUAACACAGUGUCCCAUUGAAAUUUUAAUUUUUAGAGAAUUUAUGAAUCACUGUUUCAAGAACCAGAUUGGAAAGACAAUGAAGCCUUUAUUGAGCCACUACAUUAAAAGUAUAUAUUGCUUUACUGCCUUCAAUACCAGUAUUACAUCAAUGCAUGUAUCAGAAACUUCACAGAAAUUACAUGGCAACUCUUGUAGCUAAGAAAGUAAUUCUGAGGUGUACAUUUGUCUUGCCUUUUUAAAUUUAUAAACUUGCCCUAAAAGGAGAUGCAUAUCUGGGAAACUGAACUGUCUUUUUGCAGUUUAGCCUUCAUGUAUAUAAAAUAUGCCAUUAAUUUUAUUGGGGAAGAAAUUCCAUCCAAAAAUGUUGCCUACAGCUAUGAGUUAAGAGUGUCUGUACAGUGUGUAGCUUUUAUUUUCUAAAAUCACAGAUAGGGCAUGUAUAUGACUUAUAAAUAUAUAAAUACGAUUUUGUAUUAAAAGUUUUGUAGUUUAUGGCAAAAUCUGGUCCUGUGGUAGGCUAAAUAAGUACUGUCCCUGUGAAAGGAAUGUUUGUGGCUCAUGUCAGUGUGUGAAUGCAUAGACAAUUUGAAGUUUUUGAUAUAUUUGUGAUAUUUAUCUUGAGCACUGCAAUCUCACCCCCCCCCCGCCCACCAAGGGAAUUCAAUGGGAAUGUUUAUUGUGACUUUGUCCUCUGUUGCAUUUUAAAGUUAUUUCCUGUAAUUUAUUUUCAGUACAUAAUUAAAAAUUUGUUGUAUAUAUAAAAUGAAACUUGUGAUUCUUUUUUAAGGAAUUUUUCAAGUAUGUAUUCCACUUCAUAAACCACAUUUGUUUAUAGUGAAAAGAGCAUGAGCAGGAAACACCCCAGUUGAGAGCUCUAAGGCAUUGUACCUCAAAACUAAGCUUGUAAAAAGUUACUUUUCUGUGUCUGUCUCUAUAAGGGAAAACCUAUGAUUAGCCUAGUUGUAGAUGGGGAUUGUUAAUUUCUUUCUCUCUCUUUUUUUUUUUUUGGUGGUAUAUGUAAGGCUAGCAUUUUUUCAGUACUUUUGUGGUCUUCUUUGUGAACACCGAUUAAAGUACCUAGUUUUGUUUGUUUCUUUUUUGAGACGGAGUCUCUCUCUGUCACCCAGGCUGGAGUGCAGUGGUGCGAUCUUGGCUCACUGCAACCUCCACCUCCUGGGUUCAAGUGAUUCUCCCGCCUCAGCCUCCUGAGUAGCUGGGACUACAGGUGCGUGCCACCAUUCCCGGCUAAUGUUUUCUAUUUUAAGUAGAGAUGGGGUUUCACCGUUUUAGCCAGGAUGGUCUCAAUCGCCUGACCUUGUGAUCCGCCUGCCUUGGCCUCCCAAAGUGUUGGGAUUACAGGCGUGAGCCACCGCGCCCGGCCCUUAGUUUGCUUUUUAAGCGAAGAGAAUGCAGGUGUUGAGUUGCAUGUGUGAAAACUCUGAAUUUACUUUGGUUGAUACAUCUUCGCUCCCACUCCCAUUCAGAUUCUGUUUUUAUAUGGAUUGUAUUUGUUUUCAUCUGUAUUAAAUUGCUAACUUAUCUGUUCUUAAAGAAUCCACCUGAAAAGUGUCUUUUUAUUUCUUCUGCCACCCUGUUUUAUGAAUGCUGUGGACUGUUUUUUAUGAAUGAAAAAAUAAUUUGUUGUAUAAUAGCAGAUUUUCUGAAAUUAAAGACAGCUUACUUUUAAAAAGUUA